GCCGAGUCCCCUCGCCAGAUUCCCUCCGUCGCCGCCAAGAUGAUGUGCGGGGCGCCCUCCGCCACGCAGCCGGCCACCGCCGAGACCCAGCACAUCGCCGACCAGGUGAGGUCCCAGCUUGAAGAGAAAGAAAACAAGAAGUUCCCUGUGUUUAAGGCCGUGUCAUUCAAGAGCCAGGUGGUCGCGGGGACAAACUACUUCAUCAAGGUGCACGUCGGCGACGAGGACUUCGUACACCUGCGAGUGUUCCAAUCUCUCCCUCAUGAAAACAAGCCCUUGACCUUAUCUAACUACCAGACCAACAAAGCCAAGCAUGAUGAGCUGACCUAUUUCUGAUCCUGACUUUGGACAAGGCCCUUCAGCCAGAAGACUGACAAAGUCAUCCUCCGUCUACCAGAGCGUGCACUUGUGAUCCUAAAAUAAGCUUCAUCUCCGGGCUGUGCCCCUUGGGGUGGAAGGGGCAGGAUUCUGCAGCUGCUUUUGCAUUUCUCUUCCUAAAUUUCAUUGUGUUGAUUUCUUUCCUUCCCAAUAGGUGAUCUUAAUUACUUUCAGAAUAUUUUCAAAAUAGAUAUAUUUUUAAAAUCCUUA